GACCCGACUCUGCUCCCUCCAUACUAAACACACAGACCAGACAAGCUCCUACGAAAAGCCAACGCUCCACGCCCAUUUUCGUCAGGGAAUAUGUACCCAUCGGCUUUAGAUAAAUAAGGAAACAGCAGGCUGAACCAGAACUAAGAGAAAAUUGGGCAGAGAGAAGGCAAUGGCGAGUCCACCUAGGGGCUGGGGCUGCGGAGAGCUGCUGCUGCCCUUCAUGCUCCUGGGGACGCUGUGCGAGCCAGGAUCCGGGCAGAUCCGCUACUCGAUGCCGGAGGAGCUGGACAAAGGCUCCUUCGUCGGCAACAUAGCCAAGGACCUUGGGCUGGAGCCCCAGGAGCUGGCGGAGCGCGGAGUCCGCAUCGUCUCCAGAGGUAGGACGCAGCUUUUUGCCCUGAACCCGCGAAGCGGCAGCUUGGUCACCGCGGGCAGGAUAGACCGGGAGGAGCUCUGCGCUCAGAGCCCACUGUGUGUGGUGAACUUUAACAUCUUGGUUGAGAACAAAAUGAAAAUUUAUGGAGUAGAAGUAGAAAUAAUCGAUAUUAAUGAUAACUUCCCGCGUUUCCGGGAUGAAGAGUUAAAAGUAAAAGUUAAUGAAAAUGCGGCUGCAGGGACACGGUUAGUGCUUCCCUUCGCGCGGGAUGCGGAUGUGGGUGUGAACUCUCUCCGGAGUUACCAGCUCAGCUCCAAUCUGCACUUCUCUCUGGAUGUGGUAAGCGGAACUGAUGGACAAAAGUAUCCGGAGCUGGUGUUGGAACAGCCCCUAGACCGCGAGAAAGAGACUGUUCACGACCUCCUCCUCACAGCUUUAGAUGGCGGAGACCCGGUACUCUCCGGCACCACGCACAUCCGUGUUACGGUCCUCGACGCAAACGACAAUGCGCCCCUGUUCACCCCAUCCGAGUACAGCGUGAGUGUUCCAGAGAACAUACCUGUGGGCACUCGGCUGCUCAUGCUAACCGCCACGGAUCCAGAUGAGGGAAUAAACGGGAAAUUGACCUACUCUUUUCGCAAUGAAGAAGAAAAAAUUUCGGAGACUUUCCAACUUGAUUCCAACCUGGGGGAAAUCUCAACUCUACAAUCACUGGACUAUGAAGAAUCCAGAUUCUACCUCAUGGAAGUGGUAGCUCAGGAUGGAGGCGCUCUUGUUGCCAGCGCUAAGGUGGUGGUCACAGUACAGGACGUGAAUGACAAUGCCCCCGAAGUGAUCCUCACCUCUCUGACCAGUUCGAUCUCUGAAGACUGUCUUCCCGGAACUGUAAUCGCGCUGUUUAGCGUACAUGAUGGUGAUUCUGGAGAAAAUGGUGAGAUUGCAUGCUCUAUUCCUAGGAAUUUGCCUUUUAAAUUGGAGAAGUCAGUUGAUAAUUACUAUCACCUAUUAACAACUAGGGACCUGGACAGAGAAGAGACUUCAGAUUAUAAUAUCACUUUAACCGUCAUGGACCAUGGAACCCCGCCCCUCUCUACAGAAAGCCACAUCCCCUUGAAAGUAGCAGACGUUAAUGACAACCCACCCAAUUUCCCUCAAGCCUCCUACUCCACCUCUGUCACAGAAAACAAUCCCAGAGGUGUCUCUAUCUUCUCUGUGACAGCCCAUGACCCCGACAGCGGCGACAACGCUCGAGUCACCUACUCCCUGGCUGAAGACACAUUUCAGGGGGCGCCCUUGUCCUCCUAUGUAUCCAUUAACUCUGACACCGGUGUCCUGUAUGCUCUGAGAUCCUUCGACUAUGAGCAGUUGAGAGACCUACAGUUGUGGGUGACAGCCAGCGACAGUGGGAACCCUCCACUUAGCAGCAACGUGUCGCUGAGCCUGUUUGUGCUGGACCAGAACGACAAUACGCCUGAGAUCCUGUACCCCGCCCUCCCCACAGACGGUUCCACGGGCGUGGAGCUGGCGCCUCGCUCCGCAGAACCUGGCUACCUGGUGACCAAGGUGGUAGCGGUGGACAAAGAUUCAGGCCAGAACGCCUGGCUGUCCUACCGCCUGCUUAAGGCCAGCGAGCCAGGACUCUUUGCGGUUGGGCUGCACACGGGCGAGGUGCGCACAGCGCGAGCCCUGCUGGACAGAGACGCGCUCAAGCAGAGCCUCGUGGUGGCCGUCGAAGACCAUGGCCAGCCCCCUCUGUCAGCCACCUUCACGGUCACCGUUGCCGUGGCCGACAGGAUCCCUGACAUCCUGGCUGACCUAGGCAGUAUCAAGACCCCCAUUGACCCUGAGGAUCUGGACCUCACACUCUAUCUUGUGGUGGCAGUGGCUGCAGUCUCCUGCGUCUUCCUGGCCUUCGUCAUCGUGCUGCUGGUGCUCAGACUGAGGCGCUGGCACAAGUCACGCCUGCUUCAGGCUGAAGGCAGCAGGUUGGCGGGUGUGCCCGCCUCGCACUUUGUGGGCGUGGAUGGGGUUCGGGCUUUCCUGCAGACCUAUUCCCACGAGGUCUCCCUCACCGCGGACUCGAGGAAGAGUCACCUGAUCUUUCCCCAGCCCAACUACGCAGACACGCUCCUUAGUGAAGAGAGCUGUGAGAAAAGCGAGCCUCUUCUGAUGUCUGAUAAGGUAGAUGCAAACAAAGAAGAACGGCGAGUUCAGCAAGCCCCGCCCAACACGGACUGGCGUUUCUCUCAGGCCCAGAGACCCGGCACCAGCGGCUCCCAAAAUGGCGAUGACACCGGCACCUGGCCCAACAACCAGUUUGACACAGAGAUGCUGCAAGCCAUGAUCUUGGCGUCCGCCAGUGAAGCUGCUGAUGGGAGCUCCACCCUGGGAGGGGGUGCCGGCACCAUGGGAUUGAGCGCCCGCUACGGACCCCAGUUCACCCUGCAGCACGUGCCCGACUACCGCCAGAAUGUCUACAUCCCAGGCAGCAAUGCCACACUGACCAACGCAGCUGGCAAGCGGGAUGGCAAGGCCCCAGCAGGUGGCAAUGGCAACAAGAAGAAGUCGGGCAAGAAGGAGAAGAAGUAACAUGGAGGCCAGGCCAAGAGCCACAGGGCGGCCUCUCCCCAACCAGCCCAGCUUCUCCUUACCUGCACCCAGGCCUCAGAGUUUCAGGGCUAACCCCCAGAAUACUGGUAGGGGCCAAGGCCAUGCUCCCCUUGGGAAACAGAAACAAGUGCCCAGUCAGCACCUACCCCUUCCCCCCCAGGGGGUUGAAUAUGCAAAAGCAGUUCCGCUGGGAACCCCCAUCCAAUCAACUGCUGUACCCAUGGGGGUAGUGGGGUUACUGUAGACACCAAGAACCAUUUGCCACACCCCGUUUAGUUACAGCUGAACUCCUCCAUCUUCCAAAUCAAUCAGGCCCAUCCAUCCCAUGCCUCCCUCCUCCCCACCCCACUCCAACAGUUCCUCUUUCCCGAGUAAGGUGGUUGGGGUGUUGAAGUACCAAGUAACCUACAAGCCUCCUAGUUCUGAAAAGUUGGAAGGGCAUCAUGACCUCUUGGCCUCUCCUUUGAUUCUCAAUCUUCCCCCAAAGCAUGGUUUGGUGCCAGCCCCUUCACCUCCUUCCAGAGCCCAAGAUCAAUGCUCAAGUUUUGGAGGACAUGAUCACCAUCCCCAUGGUACUGAUGCUUGCUGGAUUUAGGGAGGGCAUUUUGCUACCAAGCCUCUUCCCAACGCCCUGGGGACCAGUCUUCUGUUUUGUUUUUCAUUGUUUGACGUUUCCACUGCAUGCCUUGACUUCCCCCACCUCCUCCUCAAACAAGAGACUCCACUGCAUGUUCCAAGACAGUAUGGGGUGGUAAGAUAAGGAAGGGAAGUGUGUGGAUGUGGAUGGUGGGGGCAUGGACAAAGCUUGACACAUCAAGUUAUCAAGGCCUUGGAGGAGGCUCUGUAUGUCCUCAGGGGACUGACAACAUCCUCCAGAUUCCAGCCAUAAACCAAUAACUAGGCUGGACCCUUCCCACUACAUAAUAGGGCUCAGCCCAGGCAGCCAGCUUUGGGCUGAGCUAACAGGACCAAUGGAUUAAACUGGCAUUUCAGUCCAAGGAAGCUCGAAGCAGGUUUAGGACCAGGUCCCCUUGAGAGGUCAGAGGGGCCUCUGUGGGUGCUGGGUACUCCAGAGGUGCCACUGGUGGAAGGGUCAGCGGAGCCCCAGCAGGAAGGGUGGGCCAGCCAGGCCAUUCUUAGUCCCUGGGUUGGGGAGGCAGGGAGCUAGGGCAGGGACCAAAUGAACAGAAAGUCUCAGCCCAGGAUGGGGCUUCUUCAACAGGGCCCCUGCCCUCCUGAAGCCUCAGUCCUUCACCUUGCCAGGUGCCGUUUCUCUUCCGUGAAGGCCACUGCCCAGGUCCCCAGUGCGCCCCCUAGUGGCCAUAGCCUGGUUAAAGUUCCCCAGUGCCUCCUUGUGCAUAGACCUUCUUCUCCCACCCCCUUCUGCCCCUGGGUCCCCGGCCAUCCAGCGGGGCUGCCAGAGAACCCCAGACCUGCCCUUACAGUAGUGUAGCGCCCCCUCCCUCUUUCGGCUGGUGUAGAAUAGCCAGUAGUGUAGUGCGGUGUGCUUUUACGUGAUGGCGGGUGGGCAGCGGGCGGCGGGCUCCGCGCAGCCGUCUGUCCUUGAUCUGCCCGCGGCGGCCCGUGUUGUGUUUUGUGCUGUGUCCACGCGCUAAGGCGACCCCCUCCCCCGUACUGACUUCUCCUAUAAGCGCUUCUCUUCGCAUAGUCACGUAGCUCCCACCCCACCCUCUUCCUGUGUCUCACGCAAGUUUUAUACUCUAAUAUUUAUAUGGCUUUUUUUCUUCGACAAAAAAAUAAUAAAACGUUUCUUCUGAAAA